AGACGUUCUUUCUUUGCUGCGUCUACUGCGAGGCUGGGACACACUGGGGCCCGCUGUCGGUCUCCCGUCCUCCGACAUCUUGUCUGGAACUUCCGCCUGGCAGUCUCCAGUAGGAGUGGAGCUCUGUGCGGCGUAGUUUGGUGGAAAAACGGGCCUUGCGUCGGCCUCACCCCCAGUGUUUGUGUUUCAGAAUGAAGACUAUUCUCAGCAAUCAGACUGUCGACAUUCCAGAAAAUGUCGACAUUACUCUGAAGGGACGCACAGUUAUCGUGAAGGGCCCCAGAGGAACCCUGCGGAGGGACUUCAAUCACAUCAAUGUAGAACUCAGCCUUCUUGGAAAGAAAAAAAAGAGGCUCCGGGUUGACAAAUGGUGGGGUAACAGAAAGGAACUGGCUACCGUUCGGACUAUUUGUAGUCAUGUACAGAACAUGAUCAAGGGUGUUACACUGGGCUUCCGUUACAAGAUGAGGUCUGUGUAUGCUCACUUCCCCAUCAACGUUGUUAUCCAGGAGAAUGGGUCUCUUGUUGAAAUCCGAAAUUUCUUGGGUGAAAAAUAUAUCCGCAGGGUUCGGAUGAGACCAGGUGUUGCUUGUUCAGUAUCUCAAGCCCAGAAAGAUGAAUUAAUCCUUGAAGGAAAUGACAUUGAGCUUGUUUCAAAUUCAGCGGCUUUGAUUCAGCAAGCCACAACAGUUAAAAACAAGGAUAUCAGGAAAUUUUUGGAUGGUAUCUAUGUCUCUGAAAAAGGAACUGUUCAGCAGGCUGAUGAAUAAGAUCUAAGAGUUACCUGGCUACAGAAAGAAGAUGCCAGAUGACACUUAAGACCUACUUGUGAUAUUUAAAUGAUGCAAUAAAAGACCUAUUGAUUUGGACCUUCUUCUUAAA